AGUGUUCCUGUUGGUCUCUCACAGAUGCCGUCUAUCAGGCUGGGGAGGUUUCUUUCUGUCCUCGUUUGCUGAGAGUUUUAAAUUUCAUGAUGUAGUUUUUCCACUGCAGAAACCUAAAAGAAAACUAAGCAAAUUAGACCCCAAAACAAUAGAAUUAAAUUGAUUUUCAAAUGUUAAACCAACUCUGCUCCUGAUGUCUUGGUGGGCUUGGUUUGCUGUUUUAUGAAGAAUUCUUGGGUCCACAUUCGUGAGUGAUGUUGGAGGGUUUGCAUUUGUGUAUGAAGCUCAAGAUGUGGGGAGUGGCAGAGAGUAUGCAUUAAAGAGGCUAUUAUCCAAUGAAGAGGAAAAGAACAGAGCCAUCAUUCAAGAAGUUUGCUUCAUGGUAUCCUUUUCCUGGAACCAGGAGCCAGCACGGUGGCUUUGGCAGGCACAGGCCUGCGUCAAGCUGUGACCGCCAGUGGCCAAGAGGCUGCUCCGUGACGUUGUCUUUCAUGUGUUAAAAUCGGCUUUUUGCUUUUACCAAACCUAGUUGUAGGCGACUUCUAGGAAGAAGCAGUUUUUUCUGUUUUUUUUUUACUGCCAGGGUAAUAGUAGAAGAUUCAGAAGUGUUGGGAAUGAAGUUGUUCCUACCCAAGAGGUCUCCCUGCCCAGUGGAUGGGCUGGUUACCACAGGGGGCCCUUGCCCGGCCCGGCCCCCUCAGCUCCUCCGGAGACCUGGCUGAGAGCCGUGCAGAUGGCCUGGCUCCCACAGGCCCCGAUGUGGCUUCUCAGCCGCCCCUCUCGUCCCUUCUCAGGCUGUCCCAGCAUGACUGGGCGGGGCAUCUCCCGGCGCUGACAGAGGAUCUGGGGGCUGCACUCCCUGUCCACUGCCACAUGUCCCUCCUGAGCCUGGAGUCUUCGGCCCUGGCUGCCCUCAGACUCUGCCUCUCUUUCCUCUCCUAGCUCUGUUCACUCGGAGAGCCCGCCGGCUGCCUGAGUGUGGGUUCGGGUGGACACAGCCACGCCGCAGCCUCCCUGCGCACAGCCCCCUGAGGGCCCUGCCUCCUCCUGCCACGCGCGGGAUGGACUUUGGUGUCGCUGUGGUCAGUGCACAGAACUGUGGACAUGGUUAUGUACGUUCUCCUUUAACAAGACAACUGCAGAAAAAGCUUUCCGGCCACCCGAACAUUGUCCAGUUUUGUUCUGCAGCGUCUAUAGGAAAAGAGGAGUCAGACACGGGGCAGGCUGAGUUCCUCUUGCUCACAGAGCUCUGUAAAGGGCAGCUGGUGGAAUUUUUGAAGAAAAUGGAAUCUCGAGGCCCCCUUUCGUGCGACACGGUUCUGAAGAUCUUCUACCAGACGUGCCGCGCCGUGCAGCACAUGCACCGGCAGAAGCCGCCCAUCAUCCACAGGGACCUCAAGGUUGAGAACUUGUUGCUUAGUAACCAAGGGACCAUUAAGCUGUGUGACUUUGGCAGUGCCACGACCAUCUCGCACUACCCUGACUACAGCUGGAGCGCCCAGAGGCGAGCCCUGGUGGAGGAAGAGAUCACGAGGAAUACAACACCAAUGUAUAGAACACCAGAAAUCAUAGACUUGUAUUCCAACUUCCCGAUCGGCGAGAAGCAGGAUAUCUGGGCCCUGGGCUGCAUCUUGUACCUGCUGUGCUUCCGGCAGCACCCUUUUGAGGAUGGAGCGAAACUUCGAAUAGUCAAUGGGAAGUACUCGAUCCCCCCGCACGACACGCAGUACACGGUCUUCCACAGCCUCAUCCGCGCCAUGCUGCAGGUGAACCCGGAGGAGCGGCUGUCCAUCGCCGAGGUGGUGCACCAGCUGCAGGAGAUCGCGGCCGCCCGCAACGUGAACCCCAAGUCUCCCAUCACAGAGCUCCUGGAGCAGAAUGGAGGCUACGGGAGCGCCACACUGUCCCGAGGGCCACCCCCUCCCGUGGGCCCCGCUGGCAGUGGCUACAGUGGAGGCCUGGCGCUGGCGGAGUACGACCAGCCGUAUGGCGGCUUCCUGGACAUUCUGCGGGGUGGGACAGAGCGGCUCUUCACCAACCUCAAGGACACCUCCUCCAAGGUCAUCCAGUCCGUCGCUAAUUAUGCAAAGGGUGACCUGGACAUAUCUUACAUCACAUCCAGAAUUGCAGUGAUGUCAUUCCCAGCAGAAGGUGUGGAGUCAGCGCUCAAAAACAACAUCGAAGAUGUGCGGUUGUUCCUGGACUCCAAGCACCCAGGGCACUAUGCCGUCUACAACCUGUCCCCGAGGACCUACCGGCCCUCCAGGUUCCACAACCGGGUCUCCGAGUGUGGCUGGGCAGCACGGCGGGCCCCACACCUGCACACCCUGUACAACAUCUGCAGGAACAUGCACGCCUGGCUGCGGCAGGACCACAAGAACGUCUGCGUCGUGCACUGCAUGGACGGGAGAGCCGCGUCUGCUGUGGCCGUCUGCUCCUUCCUGUGCUUCUGCCGUCUCUUCAGCACCGCGGAGGCCGCCGUGUACAUGUUCAGCAUGAAGCGCUGCCCACCAGGCAUCUGGCCAUCCCACAAAAGGUACAUCGAGUACAUGUGUGACAUGGUGGCGGAGGAGCCCAUCACACCCCACAGCAAGCCCAUCCUGGUGAGGGCCGUGGUCAUGACACCCGUGCCGCUGUUCAGCAAGCAGAGGAGCGGCUGCAGGCCCUUCUGCGAGGUCUACGUGGGGGACGAGCGUGUGGCCAGCACCUCCCAGGAGUACGACAAGAUGCGGGACUUUAAGAUUGAAGAUGGCAAAGCGGUGAUUCCCCUGGGCGUCACGGUGCAAGGAGACGUGCUCAUCGUCAUCUAUCACGCCCGGUCCACUCUGGGCGGCCGGCUGCAGGCCAAGAUGGCAUCCAUGAAGAUGUUCCAGAUUCAGUUCCACACGGGGUUUGUGCCUCGGAACGCCACCACUGUGAAAUUUGCCAAGUAUGACCUGGACGCGUGUGACAUUCAAGAAAAAUACCCGGAUUUAUUUCAAGUGAACCUGGAAGUGGAGGUGGAGCCCAGGGACAGGCCGAGCCGGGAAGCCCCACCAUGGGAGAACUCGAGCAUGAGGGGGCUGAACCCCAAAAUCCUGUUUUCCAGCCGGGAGGAGCAGCAAGACAUUCUGUCUAAGUUUGAAGAGAAGGAGGCAGAGACUGGUGCAGAAAAUGCCUCUUCCAAGGAGAGCGAGUCUGCCCUGAUGGAGGACAGAGACGAGAGUGAGGUGUCAGAUGAAGGGGGAUCCCCGAUCUCCAGCGAGGGCCAGGAACCCAGGGCCGACCCAGAGCCCCCCGGCCUGGCAGCAGGGCUGGUGCAGCAGGACUUGGUUUUUGAGGUGGAGACACCGGCUGUGCUGCCAGAGCCUGUGCCACAGGAAGACGGGGUCGACCUCCUGGGCCUGCACUCCGAGGUGGGCGCAGGGCCAGCUGUACCCCCGCAGGCCUGCAAGGCCCCCUCCAGCAACACCGACCUGCUCAGCUGCCUCCUUGGGCCCCCUGAGGCCGCCUCCCAGGGGCCCCCGGAGGAUCUGCUCAGCGAGGACCCGCUGCUCCUGGCAAGCCCGGCCCCUCCCCUGAGCGUGCAGAGCACCCCAAGAGGAGGGCCCCCUGCCGCUGCUGACCCCUUUGGCCCGCUUCUGCCGUCUUCAGGCAACAACUCCCAGCCCUGCUCCAAUCCUGAUCUCUUCGGCGAAUUUCUCAAUUCGGACUCUGUGACCGUCCCACCAUCCUUCCCGUCUGCCCACAGUGCUCCGCCCCCAUCCUGCAGCGCCGACUUCCUGCACCUGGGGGAUCUGCCAGGAGAGCCCAGCAAGAUGACAGCCUCGUCCAGCAACCCAGACCUGCUGGGAGGAUGGGCUGCCUGGACCGAGACUGCAGCAUCGGCAGUGGCCCCCACGCCAGCCACAGAAGGCCCCCUCUUCUCUCCUGGAGGUCAGCCGGCCCCUUGUGGCUCUCAGGCCAGCUGGACCAAGUCUCAGAACCCGGACCCAUUUGCUGACCUUGGCGACCUCAGCUCCGGCCUCCAAGGCUCACCAGCUGGAUUCCCUCCUGGGGGCUUCAUUCCCAAAACGGCCACCACGCCCAAAGGCAGCAGCUCCUGGCAGACAAGUCGGCCGCCAGCCCAGGGCGCCUCAUGGCCCCCUCAGGCCAAGCCGCCCCCCAAAGCCUGCACACAGCCAAGGCCUAACUAUGCCUCGAACUUCAGUGUGAUCGGGGCGCGGGAGGAGCGGGGGGUCCGCGCACCCAGCUUUGCUCAAAAGCCAAAAGUCUCUGAGAACGACUUUGAAGAUCUGUUGUCCAAUCAAGGCUUCUCCUCCAGGUCUGACAAGAAAGGGCCAAAGACCAUUGCAGAGAUGAGGAAGCAGGACCUGGCUAAAGACACGGACCCACUCAAGCUGAAGCUCCUGGACUGGAUUGAGGGCAAGGAGCGGAACAUCCGGGCCCUGCUGUCCACGCUGCACACAGUGCUGUGGGACGGGGAGAGCCGCUGGACGCCCGUGGGCAUGGCCGACCUGGUGGCUCCGGAGCAAGUGAAGAAGCACUAUCGCCGCGCGGUGCUGGCUGUGCACCCCGACAAGGCUGCGGGGCAGCCGUACGAGCAGCACGCCAAGAUGAUCUUCAUGGAGCUGAAUGACGCCUGGUCGGAGUUUGAGAACCAGGGCUCCCGGCCCCUCUUCUGAGGCCGCAGUGGUGGUGGCUGCGCACACAGCUCCACAGGUUGGGAGCCGUCGUGGGACCUGGGUCCCCACCGUGAGGACCCCGUGGGCGACAGCAGGUGUGGCCAGGGUGGGGCUCCGAGCCCCGGGUCACCGCCCGCCCAGCGUUCCAGGCACAUGAAGAGAAAGCAUUCCAAAGCCUCUGAUUGUUGUUUCCUUUUUCUCCUCCCGAAGGAACAGCUGAUUCAUGCUCCUCCCGCAAUUGUCACGUCUGUGAUUUAUUUGGUGUUUCGGGCGUGGCCUCUGGAGCCCCGGCACGUGGUGGGCCACGCUGCUGGCGCUCAUGGGCCCUGGUGUUUGCACCGCACUUUGUAAUCAGUCCCGUGGUUGUCUGUACAGAAUUAAACUAUUUUCCGAUGA